ACUGGCCUGGCCCGCCCCCCGCACCGAGCACUCUUUCGCCCGGCCUCCGGUUCUCGCCGGCUCUCGGACCCGCCUCCGAAGACGUGGAGCGCUGCGGCGGCUGAUUUGUCAAAGAUGAAAGUGACCUUAUCAGCUUUGGAUACUUCUGAGAGUUCUUUCACACCUUUGGUGGUCAUAGAACUUGCUCAGGAUGUCAAAGAAGAAACCAAAGAAUGGCUGAAAAACAGAAUUAUAGCUAAAAAAAAAGAUGGAGGUGCCCAGUUGUUGUUUAGACCAUUGUUAAAUAAAUAUGAACAAGAAACACUAGAAAAUCAGAACUUAUAUCUUGUUGGUGCCUCCAAGAUUAGAAUGUUACUAGGGGCAGAAGCAGUGGGAUUGGUAAAAGAGUGCAAUGAUAACACCAUGAGAGCCUUCACAUACAGAACCAGACAGAACUUCAAAGGUUUUGAUGAUAACAAUGAUGAUUUCCUGACAAUGGCAGAAUGUCAAUUCAUUAUCAAACAUGAACUUGAAAAUCUUAGAGCUAAAGAUGAAAAAAUGAUCCCUGGUUACCCUCAGGCAAAGUUGUAUCCAGGAAAAUCAUUGUUGAGAAGAUUGCUCACGUCUGGCAUCGUGAUUCAGGUGUUUCCACUGCAUGACAGUGAAGCCCUGAAGAAGCUUGAGGACACCUGGUACACUCGGUUUGCUUUGAAGUAUCAGCCCAUAGACAGUAUUCGUGGCUACUUUGGGGAAACAAUUGCUCUGUACUUUGGAUUUUUGGAGUAUUUCACUUUUGCAUUAAUCCCCAUGGCUGUCAUUGGGUUACCUUACUACUUGUUUGUGUGGGAAGACUAUGACAAGUACGUGAUCUUUGCCUCGUUCAACCUCAUCUGGUCCACGGUGAUUCUGGAACUGUGGAAGCGUGGCUGUGCCAACAUGACCUACAGGUGGGGGACACUGCUCAUGAAGAGAAAGUUUGAGGAGCCCCGGCCAGGAUUUCAUGGUGUCUUGGGUAUCAAUUCCAUCACUGGGAAGGAGGAGCCUCUGUACCCCAGCUACAAGAGACAGUUGCGCAUUUACCUGGUCUCCCUGCCAUUCGUGUGCCUCUGCCUCUAUUUCUCACUGUAUGUCAUGAUGAUUUACUUCGACAUGGAGGUUUGGGCCUUGGGUCUACAUGAGAACAGCGGGUCUGAGUGGACCAGUGUCCUGUUGUAUGUGCCCAGCAUCAUCUAUGCCAUUGUGAUUGAGAUCAUGAAUCGUCUCUAUCGAUAUGCUGCCGAGUUUUUAACUUCAUGGGAGAAUCACAGAUUGGAAUCUGCCUAUCAGAACCAUCUAAUUCUGAAAGUUUUAGUGUUCAACUUCCUCAAUUGCUUUGCCUCACUCUUCUAUAUUGCCUUUGUCUUGAAAGAUAUGAAGCUUUUGCGCCAGAGCUUGGCCACUCUCCUAAUUACCUCCCAGAUCCUCAACCAAAUUAUGGAAUCUUUUCUUCCUUAUUGGCUCCAAAGGAAGCAUGGUGUGCGGGUGAAGAGGAAGGUGCAGGCUUUAAAGGCAGACAUUGAUGCUACAUUAUAUGAACAAGUCAUCCUGGAAAAAGAAAUGGGAACUUAUUUGGGCACCUUUGAUGAUUACUUGGAGUUAUUCCUGCAGUUUGGUUAUGUGAGCCUUUUCUCCUGUGUUUACCCAUUAGCAGCUGCCUUUGCUGUGUUAAAUAACUUCACUGAAGUAAAUUCAGAUGCCUUAAAAAUGUGCAGGGUCUUCAAACGUCCAUUCUCAGAACCUUCAGCCAAUAUUGGUGUGUGGCAGAUCAUAUUUUGUUUGGACACAGGUGUAAAGAGAGGGCUGAAUUGCAAGGUCAUGAGGAAUCUUUUGGGGGAAAUGGAAAUGUCCUGUGUCUUGUUUGUGGUGGUGGUGGUUUCACAGUUGGCUUUUGAAACGAUGAGUGUUAUAUCUGUGGUCACUAACUGUGCGCUGAUUGGAAUGUCACCACAAGUGAAUGCAGUCUUUCCAGAAUCAAAAGCAGACCUCAUUUUGAUUGUAGUAGCAGUGGAGGCAUAUUGCUGAAAGGAACAAAAGAAGAGGGCUUUUAAGCUUUUCUUUCUUUGAGCCCCAGAACUCCAUUUUACCAUUAAAGGAGCUGCUCAUCUUGAGUAUUGUUUUGCUGAUGAGAGGAAAUUAAUGAGGUGAGGCAUCAUUCUCAUACAUUUGAGAAUUCACUGAUCAAACUUAAGAACAAAAAUGAUCUAUUGUUUUAUGUUUUAACACUCUUUCAAAAUGUAGGUCAUGUCCAUAAAUGCAAAUGACUAUGUAGAAAGUAAUAUGCUACUGCUGCUAACCGUUUUGAGGGCACAGGGUAUUCAUGUGCUUCUAGAAUCAUCAGGAUUUGCAGAAGGGCAAUAGGAAGUGGCACACUGGGAGUGAUUGAGAAUUCUAGUGCUCUAAUGAGUGAGGGAUCACAGUUGAUAUCAGUGGAAUCAUUAAUAAAUAUAAAGUUUGUAUUUGGUACUUUUUAAAGAAAUAAUUUCAAAUUGAAAGAAGCAUUUUAAACAACUUGGAAUGUUACAUUUACUUUUGUGUUUUACUUUUAUCAGGAAUGUUUAAAUAAUCUACAAAGUAUCCUAAGCCAAGAAACUUUUUAAGAGUUUAAGCUGAAGAAGCGUUUUUAAAAUACAAAAGACUAAUAAGUAUGUGAUUAUGGUCCAAGUGAAAGUUAAUUUGUCAAUUGGAUAACAAACAUUUGUCAGUACUUAUCUUAUAGUUUUUAUGCUUUAAAAUGAGGGACAACAGACUUUCAAAACUAGGGUGCCAAGUCCUGCUUAUUCAUUCCUCUUCAGGAGAGUUUUAUAAUCUUUAAAGUCUUUGGGAAGACUUAAAGAGACUUAAUCUUUAAAGCCUUUAUCAACUGAUAUCAUAGUUACUAGUUUACACAGUAGCUGAGAUUAAUGGAAUUUGGAUUUUCAGGAUUUUUCUCCUGGUUGUCUUUGUCACUGUGUUACUAAAAUUUACUGUCAUUUAUACUCACAGUGCUACUCUAACUGUGGCCCACACUGUGCUGGUCUGAGAACUGUUAGUAGUUCACAGUAAAAUAAGGAGCUCAUACUAAAAUAUAAAUCAACAUCCUGCUUCCUUCCUUAAGAAUGUCUAGGAGGCCAGGCGCUGUGGCUCAUGUCUGUAAUCCCAGCACUUUGGGAGGCCAAAGCAGGUGGAUCACGAGGUCAAGAGAUCGAGACCAUUCUGGCCAACAUGUUGAAAUCCCGUCUCUACUAAAAAUACAAAAAUUAGCUGGAUAUGGUGGCACGUGCCUGUAGUCCCAGCUACUCAGGAGGGUGAGGCAGGAGAAUCGCUUGAACCCUGGAGGCAGAGGUUUCAGUGAGCCAAGAUGGCACCAUUGUACUCCAGCCUGGUGACAGAGCGAGACCUCUUCCCCCCUUCAAAAAAAAAAAAAAAAAAAAAGAAUGUCUAGGUAUGGUGGUUUACUUCUGUAAUCCCAGAGCUUUGGGAGGCCAAGGCAGGCAGAUUACUUGUUUGAGACCAGCCUGGCCAACAUGGCAAAAACCUAUCUCUACUAAAAAUACAAAAAUUAGCCGGGUGUGGUGGUGCACUCCUGUAAUGCCAGCUACUCUAGAGGCUGAGGCACAAGAAUCGCUUGAACCUGGGAGGCGAAGGUUACAGUGAGCUGAGAUUGUGCCACUGCACUCCAGCCUGGGUGACAGAAUAAGACUCUGUCUCAAAAAAAAAAAAAGAAAAAAAUCUACAUAUAGGAAAAAAAAGUUAGCAGAGCUCUGAGUGUGCUUAGUGACACAGUUGAUUUACAUUCUGGUACAAGUCAUCUCUUGUUCAUGGGCUGCUAACAAGUAGUGCUUUGACCUGUACUGGUUUGCAGCACUGUAAUUACAUAUAUGGUUCUCUCCUCCUUAAGACAGUUGUUGGGUUUGGAUAACAUUCAAGCUACUGAGCAGGAGCAGUGCCUGCUGUGUUGCUCCCAUCCUGACUCUCAAGCUGUCAUGCUCCACUGCCUUACUGUCUGUUUCCAGGUGGACAUUGGGACAGUGGGUCGGGGUGCAGGACUUUUCUGCAGAGAGGUGGCUUUCACCCUUUGGCUCUGUGUAUUGGUGUUGUCAGGAGUGUUGUCUGAGUCAGGGAAUUAUGUUCUACAGAGACAUGGCUGCUCCUCCCUCCCUCCCCCCAACCCCCUUCUCUCUCUCUUUCUCUCUGUCUCCCGUUCUCUCUUGCGCGCUCUCUCUCAUGCGCGCACGUUCACAUGCACACACACAUGCUCACAUACACGUGAACAGAGUUCUGAAAACAGAAGGCAUUCAGAUGGCCAUUUCAAUCAUUGGGAGAAAGAACCAUUCUCAAGCAUUUCUACUCAGCUCUUUGUCUUCUAAAAUGUAACAUUUAAUCAAAUUUUUAGAGAAAUAAUUAUUUCCCAUAUAUACCUCCCAUGUGGACAGUGGUGGCCUGCCUCAUGUCUUUUGAUAGUUUCAUUUUUGUUAUUAGCUGACAGCAUGUGCAAACUAGAAAGGUAUUCUCUUACAUAAAUAAUUAUCUUCUUUAUUUAAAUUUUAUGUACUUAUUCUCUGGGUAAUAAUGCAUUUACAUGAUUCAAAACUCAAAAGGCUCAAAAACACAGUGAUAAGAACCCUCUCCUGUCUCCCAGUCAACAAAUUCCCUUCUGUGGAGGCAGCCAGUGUGAUUGGUUUCUUAUGUUUGCUUCCAGGCAUAUUUAAUGUGCAGAUAAACAAGUAUACAAGUGUAUGUAAAUAAGCAUUAAUUCAUAAGCAGAAUUUAGUUAAUUUGUUUUACACUUAGUUGUUUAGUACAAAUAAGAAUGCUAUUGGCAAUUAACAAAAUUUUCAAUGUAAAGGAAUCCAUGUGUAAGAUGACCUCUGAUGCUAUUGAACUUUGGAAUUUAUGACUUGAAUGGUAUUUUACAAAGCAGUUUGACCUUUUCAGAAUAAGAGAAAUUCUUCCAUCAUGAAUAAAUGACAGGUUGAAGUACAAUGAUUGGUGUGCUUAUUAUUUCAGAUUUGGAUCAGUUUCACCAUCAUUUAGCAAAAGCAAGAACUGCUUAUGAAUAACAAAUAUUUUUGUCCUGCUUUUUGCCAAGGAUAGUACUGGUACUGGACUGGGGUCAAAGCUAAGGAGCUGUCUAUUUGUGCAUUUAUUAAAGUUUUUAAAAUAAGAAUGAAUUUCUUUACUGUUACUAAGGCCAAAGCUUGUUUAAAUAGAUAAUUGUGGAACUAUGGAAUAAGAAUCUGUUAGUAGAAUAACUCAACAAAAAUGCAUUGGAUUAGGGAGCUUUCGAGUGUUUUUUUAAUAAGCUGCAUAAAACUUACAUGUGAUAUAAGUAUACUUUUUGGCCUACAAAUUCUACUUCAAAUAAUUUAUUUCGAGGAGAGAUACUUGGAGGCAGGGGCAUGGCUUAGCCUCAGUGAUAUGGUUCUUUGAAUGAAAUUGCCUUAACCUUCCUGUUUUUGGCUCCUUUCUCAUUCCUGCUUUUGCUAAAUCAGCUUUUCUCUCCAACCCUUACAUAUCCGUCAGCUUUCUUGGUUUCACUUGACAACAUGCUUCUCACUUCCAUCAUCUGAAAUGUGCUACCAUUUUUUUUCUGCUAACAGCUCAUUUCUUGUUUGAGUCUUUACCGACUAUUUUGAUGAAGUCUUGGGCUCUAUCAUGCCUGGAAGCAAGGGGAGGUAUUAUUGAGCUUCUCCUGGAUUUAGGUCCUGGCUUUGCCAUAGAGGACACAAAGACAGAGAGUAUAGAGAACGUUUGUGCCAUGCAGAACAGGGAUGACCAAGUAAAGAAUCUUGCCUUUAGAACAGGGCAUGUGCUUUACAUGAAUUCCCCUCCUCACUUAGACUGAAACCUUACCAUAUCACUUUGUAUUUGAAUCUCUGGGUUGGAGAUUCCUAGAUGUUUUGGGGAGAUUGCUGUUGUUGUUUUGCAUUACUCUUUUAUGGGAAAAAGCAUUAAAAUAAUAUGAAUUAAAAUUAAUUUUGCUUCAUCUAACUAUAAAGAUAUAGCUUGAGAGAUUUUUGGUGGGUGAUGAAACUGUUCUGUACCUGAUUGUGGUGGUGGUUAUAUGAAACUAUACGUGCAUUAAAAUUCAUAAAACAAUACACCAGUCAAUUUUAUUAUAUGAUAUAAAAAACAAUUUAAUUUUGUUUUGAGAAUUUUAUGUAUCUCUGCAAAUAAAGAUACAUCUGUGGAAGUCAUUAAGGAAUCAGUAUUAUACUGGAUGAACAGUUGUAUAGCCUCCUUUAUGAAAAUUGGGAUUUCCAAUGACCUAGUCAGAUUAUUUCUUUCUAUCUACUCCUCCCUGCAUGUAUACACCUACCUGUGUUUUCAUAUUUAGUAUAAAAUUAGUUCUAAACUGAGCAAGGAUGGCAAGGCAGCGAUGAUGGCUUUUUCUCCCCUAAUCUUUGGAAAGAAUUUUAAGCCAUUAAACGUGAGAAGUUUAAGCGAAGGCAUAGCAUUUGCAAUUAUCAGAGCAUCAGUGACUAUUGCCUCUUUAUUUAGACAGUCUGAGUCCUCUGUCCUUUUGACUAUGGGACCUUUAUCCUUUUGCAUUACUAAGAGCUUUAGGGGAAUAUUUGAGACUUUCAUCCUAGCUGCUUGUGAUUCAGCUCUUCUCCUUGUUGGCAAGGUACAGUUGAUGUCAUACAUAGGGCUGGCAGAUGAAUCAGCAGGAUGCUGCUUGGCAAUGUGGACGGGGUGACUGAGUGAAGAGGGUUUAAGUUUGUUGGGUGAAGCAUCACUGAGCUUGUGACAAUGCUCUUGGCUCUUUCAUGACUAUGGGUUUUGUUUUUUUUUUUUUGAGACAGGGUCUUGUUCUGUCACCAGGUUGGAGUGCAGUGGCCGAUGGCCCAAUCUCGGCUCACUGCAACCUCCGCCUCCUGGGCUCAGGUGAUCCUCCUGCCUCAGCCUCCUGAGUAGCUGGGACUACAGGUGCUCACUACCACGCCUGGCUAAUUUUUGUAUAUUUUAGUAGAGAUGGGGUUUCACCAUGUUAGCUAGGCUGGUCUCGAACUCCUGACCUGAAGUGAUCUGCCCACCUCAGCCUCCCAAAGUGCUGAGAUUACAGGUGUGAGCCACUGCGCCCGGCCUCAUGAUUAUGCUUUAAUUACCAUGUAAAUGACAAAUCGUCAGAUCACACAUUUUUAUUUUAGAGACCUAUAUAUUUAUUUUUUAUACCAAUAAGAAACCUAAAAUGCAGCAUAGUAGCUUUUCAUUUCAUAUUUUAAAAUGUUGAUGCAAGAAAAGACUCUUCCAUAGACAUUAGAAGAUAGAGAACUUUAUCUGAGUCAUGAGAAUCCCUUAUUUUACCUUUAUUCUCACAAAAUAAUUUGAAAAAGCUGGAAUAAUUUAUAAGCCACUAUUAAGAUGACAUAGAUCUUGGUGAAUUCUUUAGAUAAAGAUUAAGCCAGAACGUGUAAUUUAAAGAUUGUUAAAAACAUUUCUCCAAAGUAAAAUAAUUUGCUUAAAAAUGUAGGUUGGUUCUUGAAGAUCUGUCAUUUUGUUUUGUCUUCAAAAUAGUUGAAAUAUUAGCUCUACAGCAUGUAGACAUACUUGAAAGUUAGAAUACUUCUGCUAGUGACCACAGACUUAUUUUUUGUCUUUUUGCCUAGAGUUUAUUAGUCAUAUUACACAGGUUUUAGUUAAAAGAAUACCCAAGUUUGGCCUUUUACAUACAUAACAUGCCUUUUGAUAUCAACACUUUUUCUAUGACCUAACAUAGGAUUAGGUUUUUGAAUAUUCUGUGUGUGCCCAAGGAGAAGGUAUAUCCUCUCUUAUCAGUGUAAUGUUUUAUUUGUACACACACACAUACACACACACACACACAUUAGUCCCAGCUUAUCUGCAAAGGAUGGUUCCAAGACUCCCAGUGGAUGCCUGAAGCAAUAGAUAGUAUUGAACCCUGUAUACACUGUUUUUUCUUAUAUAUACAUACCUAUGAUAAAGUUUAAUUGAUAAAUUAGAGACAGUAAGAUAUUAACAACAAUAGUAGAACAAUCAUUAUAAUAUACUUUAAUAAAAGUUAUGUGAACAUGGGGUCUCUCUCUCAAAAUACUGCUUUAAUAAAAGUUAUGUGAAUGUGGGGUCUCUUUCUUUCUCUGUCUCUCAAAAUACUAUGAUAUUUUUGGACUGCAGUUGACCA